AGUUUAGCAACUGCAGUUCUUCUGUGUAGCAUGGGCUGCUUCUCCACAACCGCGAGAAGCCCGGCUGCCUGUUUAUUCUGGAGCAGCAGCAGUUGACAGACGGAGAGGCAGUGACUCUGCACCCAGCAAUCCCUCUGCAGACAGCUCCCACAGGAGUCAUGCCCAGUGUGUGAAGAAGCAAUUAUGUCUCCGGUACCCUCUCUCCCACCUUCAGCCACUGCAUAAAAUUGUCACAGAUUAAAUCAAAUUGUUCAGCCAUUUCAUUAGAGAGACUCCAGCUCUCAUUCUCUGGGGGCAUUUUCACUCUUCUCAAAUAAAAGCCUCUUUCAGAUAAGUUAACUCCUUCUUGAAGACUAUAGAAAGCCACUGAGCAGACCACUAAAGGGCUGUUGAGACCUGAUGGUUUUUUUGGUGGUCAUAUAGCCCGGACACAGCACCUUCUGUCACGGAGACUGAACUCUGACUGGCAAGACAGAACGGGUGGGAGUGCAAGCAACAGCAGAGAAGACUGUUAGCGUAGAAGAACCCAGGCCUCUAGGACUGACUCAAACUUUCUCAUCUCAUGACCCUGGGUACGUUUCUUUUCCUGGAUGAACCUCAUUUCUCCAAUCUCAACAAUGCAAGUUUAAAGGCUUUUUUUUUUUUCUGUAGUGGAUUCCAGGAAUCCCUCCAAAAUAGCAUGCAAAUGCUUGAGAAGAAUGAUAGAGCUGUUGGGAAGAGAGAGGAUGUUGGAAUUCUCUUUGAUGGAUAGCAAAAUCUUGUUCUGACUUGUUUUCUGGAAUGGUUGACAUAAAGGAGGGGAGAGAUCAGACAUUGUGGUGGGAGCCUGCUGCUUAGAAGCAGCUUGGGGGAGGGGAUGGAGGGGAGGGAAGGCUGGCAGGGCUGGGGGCACCCUGGCAUCUGGAGGGGUGGAACUUAUGGGGGCGGGGUUCUGGGCACAAUCACUAGGUGUUGAAUGACAGUUGAUGAGUCAGGCUGAAAGGACAGGAAGGCAUUGUUGGGACAGUUUGCUGUGUCUGGGGACACUGGAGAUGGUGGCAAAUGGGCAAGGCCAGCACACAUGUGGUUUCAGAGUUAGUUCUGCAUGUUGAGAACUUUCCCCAGAAGCCCAAAGGCCUCGGUGAUGAUAGACAAGGAGGCUGAGGAACCAAGGCAGCUGGCAGGUACCAGGAAGCCCAAGGAGCAGGACAGAGGCAGGCAUGUGCAGGACAGCCUGUGCAUGUCACAUGUGUGUUUCCCAAGGCCUGUGCGUAGCAGAGCAGCCUGUGCAUGUCACACACAUGCUUCCUGAGACCUGUGUAAGACACCCUGUGCGUGUCACAUGUGUGCUUCCUGAGGCCUGUGCAAAGCAGCCUCUGCAUGUCAUACGCAUGCUUCCCAAGGCCUGUGCAGAACAGCCUGUGCAUGUCACACCCAUGCUUCCUGAGGCCUGUGUACGACACCCUGUGCGUGUCACAGGCAUGCUUCCUGAGGCCUGUGCAGAGCGGCCUCUGCAUGUCACACGCAUGCUUCCCGAGGCCUGUGCAGGACAGCGCCUGUGGCUACAAUCCCCUCAGGGCCAGGGAGGCCUGGUUUGCCUCUUCCCUCUUGCCUGACCCGGGCCUCGGAGGCAGCACACUCCCACUACGUGGGUGGGAUCCUGACUUCCUCAAGGCUCUAGCCCAGGGCCCGGCACCGGGGAGAUGCCCAGGAAGUGUCUGCUGAACUGCGGGGAAUGUGGGUUGGAGUCACGCCACCUGCUGUGUUUCUGUAAGCAUUUUGGGGAAGCACAUUUCUUGGGUACCUUCGCCAGGCUCAGGAAUGGAGACAAGGCCAAUGUAUCCCUGCCCUCCUGGACUGCAGGUGUUGCUGUUAGAACCUGCCCAGCUGCUAGAAAGUUCCUACCAGGGUCAGAGGCCCUGGGAUUUUGGGUGCGCAUGUUUUUCUGGUUUGUGAGGAGGGUAGGGGCAAGCAUGAAGAAAGAAGGGCCCGAGCCUCAAAUUUGCAAGGGCAUCCUCUUUUCUAGUCACAAAGAUCAACAGGAUCCAAAAAGGAUGGGAUUUGCGCUUCACUUUAAACAUGCUGCCCGUUCUAGCCAACCCUUCUGUGGUGCACUAUGAGUUUAUAGCUUUUGCGAGCCUGGUCAUUGUCUUCGGAAUAUUACUAUGCAUUAGCUUGAGCAGUAAGUGACAAGUUGUUCAUGUAAAUGUCUAAGAUAUACGGACUUUUAAACAACUCUCAUUUUGGUGUUCCUUGUUUCUUAAUAUAGUAGGAGUCUCACCUCACACCACCCCUUCCCUUAAAUUAUGGAGCAGUGCAGACCUCCCUCAACCCGGGGAGGGCCUUGCUCUGAGAGUGUACUUCUUUCCAGAACCUGUACACAUAGGGCAUGGAGACAGGACUCAAGGCCAGGGUGGGAGUUGGAUGGGCUGACUUUUGUGCCCUUCAUAAGGUUUGAUCCUGAGCUGCAGACACAGGUAGGUGGGAGAUUAGUUUCCAUUUGGGCUGGAGGCCGAUGGGGGGACCCUGUUCCGUCUCUUCUCUUUGACCCCACAAAGCAGGCAGAGCUCUAUUUAUGAAUGUGGCCUUCCUCUCUGUGCUUCCACCAUCCAGAGGGAACGUGGCUUCCCUAAAACCCUAUUCUCUGAUAAUCUAUGUCCCUUUCCAAAAUAUUUGUAUGAAGGUCCAGACUUGGAAAUUUUAUCAUUAAGGACAAUCAGUAAACAGAGUAAUAACUAACAUGUAUUCUAUGCCACGCCACGUUCAAAGUGGUUCCCAUGCUUUAUCUCAGUUAAUUUUGUGACCAUAACCCAACACUGUUCAAUUAGUGUUCCCCAAAACAGUCAGAAAAAGGUUAAUGACUUGGCCAGGCAUGGAGGCUUAUGCUUGUAAUCCCACCACAUUGGGAGGCCAAGGCAGGUAGAUCACCUGAGAUCAGGAGUCCAAGAUCAGCCUGGCAACAUGGUGAAACCCCAUCUCUACUAAAAAUACAAAAAUUAGCUGGGUGUGGCAUGUGUGCCUGUAAUCCCAGCUACUUGGAAGGCUGAGGCAGGAGAAUCGCUUGAACCCGGGAGGCAGGGUUGCAGUGAGCCGAGAUCGUGCCAUUGCACUCCAACCUAGGCGACAGAGUGAGACUGCGUCUCAAAAAAACAAAAACAGAAAAGGUUAAUGACUUGCCCGAAGUCAUCUAGCUUGUAAGUACACAGCCAGAAUUUAAGCCUGGGUGGUUAACUUGAAAACCGUUAUGGAGCAACCCAGAGAUUUAGCAUCAGUGGUUCAAAUCUCAGUUCUACAAUUACUUGCCAUGUGACCUCAUACAAGUCACUUACCCCUUCUGAGACUCAGUUUCCCUCACUGCACAAUGGGCUUAAGCAUGAUGCAAGGACUUUACAAUGAUCAAAAGUAACAGUUGAUGUGAAAGGGCUUCAGCAGCAUGCAGCCAGUCCACAGAGUUGUUAUGAAGUUUUCCUCUUUCAUCCUUUGUUAAAGCAUGCUGACAAACUCAAAAGGAUGACAAAAAGUAGCAGCAGAAAGUACCUUCUCCUCAUGCCUUUGGUUGUACAGACACACAACUCCUGUACUCCAAAUUCCUGGCACACAGAGUUGAUGGUGAGGGCCCCUGAGUGGAGAUACUUUCUGGGCCACCUGAAAUGCUGCUUGGUUUCUCACACAAACCCUGCUGUGGCUGCUUACCAUCCUCAGCAAGGGUGCGGAGGAAUGGAAACUUUUGCCACCAACAGCAUUUGCUAGCAACUUCCCUCUCUGUGGUUUUUCUGUCAUUCCCUUGAUAAAAGAACUUGAGCUGCGCAAAAGUAACCAAUCUUCACCAAUCUCAUCUUCACAUAUAAACAGCCGCCUUUCAAGAAGCAAGCUGCCAGAAAAAUGAUGCACGAUGCUCUCUAAACUGGGUCAUUCUCCACUUGGAGGGCUCAGGGCACGGUUGACUUUCCCCGUCUGUCUCCUAUACCACAGGCUCUGGGCAUCACCAGCGGCCCCAGGGAAAAAGAAAGAAAUGGGAAACAGCAUGAAAUCCACCCCUGCGCCUGCCGAGAGGCCCCUGCCCAACCCGGAGGGACUGGAUAGCGACUUCCUUGCCGUGCUAAGUGACUACCCGUCUCCUGACAUCAGCCCCCCGAUAUUCCGCCGAGGGGAGAAACUGCGUGUGAUUUCUGAUGAAGGGGGCUGGUGGAAAGCUAUUUCUCUUAGCACUGGUCGAGAGAGUUACAUCCCUGGAAUAUGUGUGGCCAGAGUUUACCAUGGCUGGCUGUUUGAGGGCCUGGGCAGAGACAAGGCCGAGGAGCUGCUGCAGCUGCCAGACACAAAGGUCGGCUCCUUCAUGAUCAGAGAGAGUGAGACCAAGAAAGGGUUUUACUCACUGUCGGUGAGACACAGGCAGGUAAAGCAUUACCGCAUUUUCCGUCUGCCCAACAACUGGUACUACAUUUCCCCGAGGCUCACCUUCCAGUGCCUGGAGGACCUGGUGAACCACUAUUCUGAGGUGGCUGAUGGCCUGUGCUGUGUGCUCACCACGCCCUGCCUGACACAAAGCACGGCUGCCCCAGCAGUGAGGGCCUCCAGCUCACCUGUCACCUUGCGUCAGAAGACUGUGGACUGGAGGAGAGUGUCCAGACUGCAGGAGGACCCCGAGGGAACAGAGAACCCGCUUGGGGUAGACGAGUCCCUUUUCAGCUAUGGCCUUCGAGAGAGCAUUGCCUCUUACCUGUCCCUGACCAGUGAGGACAACACCUCCUUUGAUCGAAAGAAGAAAAGCAUCUCCCUGAUGUAUGGUGGCAGCAAGAGAAAGAGCUCAUUCUUCUCAUCACCACCUUACUUUGAGGACUAGCCAAGAACAGACACAAUGGUUCAUGCCCAAAAGGAACAGAAGUUCCAACUAUUGCCUGGGAUCUUGCGAAAAGCGAGGUUCCCUGAUCCCUGGGAGCCUCACGUAUUUUAGAAGCCAAGAGAAGCCACAUGGAGACUCAAAUUCGCAUCUUCUCUAUCCACAUCAUGACCAAAGGAACCCCUCCCUGGUGUCUGAUCAGGGCUGUGGCAUCACGAAACAUUGGAUCAUGACAUGUCGGGCGAUGCUUGGAAGAGCCCAGCAUGUAUGUAUGCACACAUUGUGUGUGUGGGAAGGACAAAGCCACUCUCACAAGAAAGGGCACCAGGACUGCUCUCCAAGGAACUGGACCUGUCCAGACAGUUACACUCCAAGGUCAUUGGAGAGAACUUCUGUAUGGGCAAGCCUGAGAGGGAGAGGAAACAAAAGCUGUGUCCUGGCAGAAGGUCUGGGUUUGCAGAUGGGUGCCCUGAAUGGAACUACUUUAACUAAUCCAUAGGGACUUCUGGUAUGCUUUCCUCUCUUUUUAAAGGAACUUCGUGACACUAAACAUUAGCCCAAAGGACUUCUUAGCCUUCAAUUGGGAGAUACCUUUGGUCUGCUCCUGCACCAAAGCCAUAUGGGUGGAAGUCAGUUGGCCUCCCUGGUUCUGCAGAGGGCCAGAAGAAUGAGAGAGAGGAAGACUGCUGGCAGGGAAAUCGAGGAGGCGAGACUAGAACUGCACCAGCUUCCCUGAUGUCUGCAGCCAUGGCUUUGCAGCGCAGACAGAGCUUCUCUGGGAUGCUGGGAUUCUUGCCUGUAUGAAUGCAUCAAGUAUUCAUUUAUUGCCCGAAUAGGCAUUGCAUUAAGUCCUCUGUAAGGUGUCAGGCAAGCCAAAAAAAAAAAAAAGAUGCGUAAGUCCUAACCCCCAACAGAGGUGUUCACAGUGUAGACAGGGAAAAAAUGUAUAAACAAAUGUGUAAAAAGAGAAAUCAGCUCAUGGCUUAGGAUGGAAUUAGAGACAGGUGAGGGACACUCAGGAGCUCAUUUUCCAGCUGCUCUUCAGAGUGGAAGGGCUGGCUGGAUCGGGUAGGUAAGAAUAGCUGGAUUUUUUAGAAAAGAAAUGGAUACAGUCUAAAGAAUUAACUCACCCGGUACUUUAUUCUAAGAAGGGUCUGGCAUCCAUAUGAGGAAAAAUGCUCAGCUCCAGGAAAGAUGGGGAGUCCAAGUGGAUUAAUGAUGUCAUGCAUAAUUUUAAGAGACAAGGGAGAAAACACAAUGUAUAGCCAGAGAAGGAGAAGCUCCCAUCCAAAUCCUACUAGGAAGAGAGUGGGCUGCAGAUGAAUCUGUGACUCAUGUUUCCCUGUUUCAAAGGGAUCCUGGGGAAGGAGGGGAACAUGCUUGCAGUAUCUCUCCCUGUCUGUCUGCUCACAUAAGCAUUCCGUCCAUCUGAGCUCAUCGUGCUACUGGUAUGUGUAUGUGCAGUUACACAGUUUUCUGUAUCAUAGAUUCUAGUGUGUUUAUACAAGGAGACAUCUGUGGUUUCCCCAACCGUUCCAAAAGGCUAUUUCAAAGGAACCAGCCAACGUAUGAGAAAUGAAUGUAACACUGUGGACAUUGACUUCCCGCAUAAGGCAGGGUGACCCCCUGAACUCCAGAUGUCUGCACAGUAUCUUAUGUGUUGUUUUCCGUUGUGACGAAUGUGAUUGGAACAUUUGGGGAGCACCCAGAGGGAUUUCUCAGUGGGAAGCAUUACACUUUGCUAAAUCAUGUAUUUAUUCCUGAUUAAAACAAACCUAAUAAAUAUUUAACCCUUGGCA